AGAAGCCCCUCCUUGGCACCCCCUCUUCCCUGACUGCUGUCCCCUACCCAGCCUUGCCCCCUUCAUCCUUUUGCGUUUGGUAUUGAGACUCUCCUAGACUCUACUCCUCUUUCUUUUGUAUGGACAGUUCCCCUUCAGUCCCAUCCCCCUACACAUACACCCAGCCGGGGCCAAAUUUAUACUUAUAUAAAAGUUGUAAAUAUGUGAAAUUUUAUCCCUGUGCCCUUUCCCCACCUCAGGCCCUACCCCUGGACCCUCCCCAACCUUCCUUCUCUCUUCUUUGGCUGUUGUAAUUAUCUGGGGUUUGUACUGUACAUAUCCGGGGUGUGUGUGUGUGGGCUGGGGGCAACCCUUCUGUACAGAGCUUCCUGGCCCCCUCCCCCCCCGCCCCUCUGCUUCCCUCCCCACCCACCACCUCAAGGGUAGGGAGUUGCUCUUCCUACCUGUUUUAUUUUGUUUUCUCGUUCUCCCUCCCCACCCCACUCCCAGCCUUAUCUAUCCCCCCUCACUGUCCCCUUUUCUCCACUCCCAGCCCCAUUUCCUUUUUUUCUGGAGUGUGUGGUGAAACAGAAAAAAACAUGUUUAAUAAACGGAGAUUGUUCUUUUAUCGCUGUGCCGACUUUCUUAGGCAGGGCUCUCCAGACCUGUACGGUGGUAAGAUCUGCUUUCUGAAAGGAAGCUGACAGCCUGAGAGGAAAACCGUAUAUCCCCACCUGAUGCCACACUCUCCUCAUAGAAUGUCACUCUCCCCUCCCAAUGAGAUUUUUUAUAUUUUAGAGCAGGAGUUUUGCACCGGCCAAACUUCUCCAAUCUAACUCUCCCCUCACCACUGUGUCACUUAGUCCGAGGCCAGGAACAGCGGCGUUAUCUGAUAAAAGAGUUCAUGUAUAUAUCCACAUUUAUCUCUUUUAAAAAUUACCUAGAAAUAAGGUUUCUUUAAUUGCUGGUUAAAAUGCUCCCGUGCAGAAAACAGGAAAGAACCUGCCUGGUUCCUUAGCAAAUCUGAGUUCCAGUCCCAGGUCCACUACUAUUAGCUGAGUGACGCUUCCAGCCCGUUUCCCCCGCCUGGAAACUGAGGACGGCAACCCCCACCCUCGCAGGGCCGGUGGGAAGACACAAAGUGAUGUGGGCAAGUGCCAGGCCCACAUGCCUUCAUCCCGCGUGGAGUCUACCCCCAAGCCCUUCUCCUCUUCCCAAUUCUUGUCACCUUCGAGGAGGCCAUGGAAACCCCAACACCUUUGCCGCCUGUACCCGCCUCCCCGACCUGCAACCCAGCCCCACGGACAAUCCAGAUCGAGUUCCCACAGCAUAGCUCGUCUCUGCUGGAAUCUCUGAACCGCCACAGGCUAGAGGGAAAGUUCUGUGAUGUGUCCCUCCUGGUGCAGGGCCGGGAACUUAGGGCUCAUAAAGCAGUGUUAGCUGCUGCCUCUCCUUACUUCCAUGACAAGCUGCUUCUGGGGGAUGCGCCUCGUCUCACUCUACCGAGUGUCAUUGAAGCCGAUGCCUUCGAGGGGCUGCUCCAGCUCAUUUAUUCAGGGCGUCUCCGCCUGCCACUGGAUGCUCUUCCUGCUCAUCUCCUUGUGGCCAGUGGCCUUCAAAUGUGGCAGGUAGUAGAUCAGUGCUCAGAAAUUCUUAGAGAAUUAGAAACUUCAGGUGGUGGAAUUUCAGCCCGUGGAGGAAACUCCUACCAUGCCCUUCUUUCCACUACAUCCUCUACAGGAGGCUGGUGCAUUCGCUCUUCGCCUUUCCAGACCCCAGUACAGUCCUCUGCUUCUACUGAAAGCCCUGCUUCCACUGAGAGCCCUGUGGGAGGGGAGGGAAGUGAACUGGGAGAAGUGCUGCAAAUUCAGGUGGAAGAAGAAGAGGAGGAGGAGGAAGAUGAUGAUGAUGAGGACCAGGGGUCAGCCACACUCUCUCAGACUCCUCAGCCCCAGAGAGUAUCAGGGGUUUUUCCCCGUCCUCAUGGACCCCACCCACUGCCCAUGACUGCUACUCCCCGAAAGCUUCCAGAGGGUGAGAGUGCACCACUUGAGCUUCCUGCCCCUCCUGCACUGCCCCCCAAAAUCUUCUACAUUAAGCAGGAACCCUUCGAGCCUAAGGAGGAGAUAUCAGGAAGCGGAACUCAGCCUGGAGGAGCAAAGGAGGAAACCAAAGUGUUUUCUGGAGGGGACACUGAAGGGAAUGGGGAGCUAGGGUUCUUGUUGCCUUCAGGGCCAGGGCCAACAUCUGGGGGAGGGGGUCCAUCCUGGAAACCAGUGGAUCUUCAUGGGAAUGAAAUCCUGUCAGGGGGUGGAGGACCUGGGGGAGCAGGCCAGGCCGUGCAUGGGCCUGUGAAGCUAGGGGGGACACCCCCUGCAGAUGGAAAACGCUUUGGUUGCCUGUGUGGGAAGCGGUUUGCAGUGAAGCCAAAGCGUGACCGGCACAUCAUGCUGACCUUCAGCCUUCGGCCUUUUGGCUGUGGCAUCUGCAACAAGCGCUUCAAGCUGAAGCACCAUCUGACAGAGCACAUGAAGACCCAUGCUGGAGCCCUGCAUGCCUGUCCCCACUGUGGCCGUCGGUUCCGAGUCCAUGCCUGUUUUCUCCGCCACCGGGACCUAUGCAAGGGCCAGGGCUGGGCCACUGCCCACUGGACUUACAAGUGACUGCUGAGGCUAUACACUAGCUUCUAGAACAAGAUAACCACUGCUGCUGAUGGAUACUUUUCCCUCACUGCCAUGGCACACCAGUCAUGGAUCUUGUAAUCAUGCCAAGAGAAUAGAUACAUUAUGGACCUCUUGUUCUUAGAUAUGGGCCUCUCAGCCUGGCAGAUGUGGAAACUCAAAUUUCUCGUCCCACUCCAGGUUUUGGCUAGCCAACCCUGCAGGAAAGUGGUUUAUAGGCCAUUCAUACUUAAGUUGAUCACUUGCCCAUGGUGGACAUUUUUGUGGUGGUGAUGUCCAUUAAGGAAACCAGAUUUUCAAUUAUUUAGUGAGAGAAGAGUUAGAGCAAAAGACAGUGGUAAAUGUUUUAUUCCGUCUCCAUGAGGAAUUGAAGGAGUUGGUCUCCACCUAGAGAUACAUUUGAUUUACAGCUUAAGUAAUUCAGAGGCUAAGCUCUAAGCUUUUUUCUCUCAUUGCUGGAAUGAUUUAAGCAGAAGUCCUUUUGUGUACUUUUAAAAUUGUAUCUUUCCAGGAGCCCCUCAGAUUGUACCUUGCUUUCUCACCAAUAGACACCUUCCCGACACUUUUUUAAUGUUGUAGCUGAGCACUUUAACAAGUUGAGCAUUCCAUGUUUCAUUCUUAGAACCUUCUUUAAUAGAGGGUCUUCCCUCAACAGCCUGUGCCUCUGGUCUACCUUUGACCACCACUGAUAACUAAUAUAUUGGUCACAAUGACUGGAAUGUGACUAGUGAUCUCAGGAGAUGGCACUGUCCUAAAGUGCUGUCAGGGUGGCACCACUGCUCUCUGAACAACUUACCUUGGUCAGAGGGACUCAGGUUUGGGACAGCACAAGCUGAAGGCUGGAGAGUAACUUGCAUAGUAGGACCAUACCUCUUCCUUUCCCAUCCCACCCACAUAUGAUAGACAGCCCCUCUGUUGAGAUAUGGAGGGGACAGAUACUGGAAUCGGGGGUGGGACUUGCAGUUACUUAAAAUUUUUUAAUAAACUGUGCCCUGAAACCUAAA